CUUUCUGCCCACACUAGACAUGGCGCUUGCCAGCGUGUUGGAGAGACCGCUACCGGUGAACCAGCGCGGGUUUUUCGGACUUGGGGGUCGUGCAGAUCUGCUGGAUCUAGGUCCAGGGAGUCUCAGUGAUGGUCUGAGCCUGGCCGCGCCAGGCUGGGGUGUCCCAGAAGAGCCAGGAAUCGAAAUGCUUCAUGGAACAACCACCCUGGCCUUCAAGUUCCGCCAUGGAGUCAUAGUUGCAGCUGACUCCAGGGCUACAGCGGGUGCUUACAUUGCCUCCCAGACGGUGAAGAAGGUGAUAGAGAUCAACCCAUACCUGCUAGGCACCAUGGCUGGGGGCGCAGCGGAUUGCAGCUUCUGGGAACGGCUGUUGGCUCGGCAAUGUCGAAUCUAUGAGCUUCGAAAUAAGGAACGCAUCUCUGUAGCAGCUGCCUCCAAACUGCUUGCCAACAUGGUGUAUCAGUACAAAGGCAUGGGGCUGUCCAUGGGCACCAUGAUCUGUGGCUGGGAUAAGAGAGGCCCUGUGUCUGAAGUUCUGUGCUUGAAACCUAAGUCAUUUGGAAUGUACUUGUUUUGUGGGUGUGCUGAGAGGAUCGGCAACAUGGCAAGGCCUCUACUACGUGGACAGUGAAGGGAACCGGAUUUCAGGGGCCACCUUCUCUGUAGGUUCUGGCUCUGUGUAUGCAUAUGGGGUCAUGGAUCGGGGCUAUUCCUAUGACCUGGAAGUGGAGCAGGCCUAUGAUCUGGCCCGUCGAGCCAUCUACCAAGCCACCUACAGAGAUGCCUACUCAGGAGGUGCAGUCAACCUCUACCACGUGCGGGAGGAUGGCUGGAUCCGAGUCUCCAGUGACAAUGUGGCUGAUCUACAUGAGAAGUAUAGUGGCUCUACCCCCUGAAAGAGGGUGGAUGCAGCUGCUUGUGUUUCUUGGGGUGACUGUCAUUGGUAAUACGGACACAGUGACCCAUCCUCCAUCCUAUUUAUAGUGGAAGGGCCUUCAAUUGUAUCAGUACUUUUUUUUAAGCUCUGGCACAUUGACCUCUAUGUGUUACCAGUCAUUAAUGAGCUGCUGCAGAGGUGACUAUUUGUUUUACUUUCUUGGAUGUUAACAUUACACUACUCACUACUCAA